AAGCUAUAAAGAAGUUACGGGGGGCAGUUUUCGGCUUCCAAUUAGGAAUAAUAGUGAACUGGCUUCGUAGCAACUACGGAGGACCAGGAUUCUAAAAUCACCUCACUCGUCCCAAAGCUUGCAUCCUCCUCUUUCUGCCACGCACCCCUCCUCCAAUUCAUGAUCCAGAAAAGGGAGCCGGGAAUGCUCUGCUCCUCUCUGCCGGUGGGAAGCGGAGAGGCCGGCGGUGUCGCUGGGUUGGACGGUAGGCAUGAGAACAGUUAAGAGAUGGGCGCCCCCGAAACCUCUGCCGCUUGUGGGGACUGAAGGGCCUUGAAAGAGUUGUCUGGGGUUCCUGCUCUUCCCAAAGGGGCUCGGAGAUACCUUAAAUGCCGCGAGACUGAAGAGCAAACGUCAGGGAUUAUUAUGUCGAUUUUCCGAGGACCAGGGUUCGCAGCUGGCAGUAGAAGAAAAGGCUGGCUCCUCAGGGGUCCCACUGGCAUUUGAUACCCUGAACGACCCUCAGGAUUGCCCAAAUUCGGUGGAUCGCCCAAAUUCGGUGGAUCAGCAACUUUCCUAUACUGCAUCCCGAAUUUUCAAAGAACAUAUUUUCCGUUCACCCCCGCUGGUCUUUUACUGCCAUCAAUACACUGUUCUUGGUGCAAAUACUUCAGCCUCUUUAUUCAAAGUAUGUUUUAUGUUUUUGCCAAAUAUGAUCUCUAAUUGAAAGUUUAUUUUUGGUUUUGGAUGAAUCUGCGGAGCUUAAGUUGUGAGAAGAAAGGGGGAACAAGACACAAUGAAAGAAAAGUCCAAAAAUGCUGCGCGGACUAGGAGGGAGAAGGAAAACAGUGAAUUUUAUGAACUGGCUAAAUUACUGCCUUUGCCCUCGGCUAUCACCUCGCAGCUGGACAAAGCAUCCAUAAUCAGACUCACGACCAGCUAUCUCAAAAUGAGAGUGGUGUUCCCAGAAGGGCUCGGCGAGGCGUGGGGCCACUCAAGUCGGACCAGCCCCCUGGACAACGUUGGCCGAGAACUGGGCUCCCAUCUGCUCCAGACCCUGGAUGGCUUCAUCUUCGUGGUAGCCCCAGAUGGGAAGAUCAUGUACAUCUCAGAGACAGCCUCAGUCCACUUGGGUCUUUCUCAGGUAGAGCUGACCGGAAACAGCAUUUAUGAAUACAUUCACCCGGCAGACCACGACGAGAUGACGGCGGUGCUCACCGCCCAUCAACCCUACCACUCUCACUUCGUGCAGGAGUAUGAGAUCGAGCGCUCCUUCUUCCUGAGGAUGAAGUGCGUCUUGGCCAAGCGUAACGCCGGCCUCACCUGUGGCGGCUACAAGGUCAUCCACUGCAGCGGCUACUUGAAGAUCCGCCAGUACAGCCUGGACAUGUCCCCCUUCGACGGCUGCUACCAAAACGUGGGCCUGGUGGCCGUGGGCCACUCGCUGCCUCCCAGCGCCGUCACGGAGAUCAAGCUACACAGCAAUAUGUUUAUGUUCCGCGCCAGCCUGGACAUGAAGCUCAUCUUUCUGGACUCCAGGGUGGCGGAGCUGACGGGGUACGAACCUCAGGACCUGAUUGAGAAGACUCUGUACCACCAUGUGCACGGCUGCGACACCUUCCACCUGCGCUGCGCGCACCAUUUGCUGCUGGUGAAGGGACAGGUGACCACCAAGUACUACAGGUUCCUGGCGAAACACGGCGGCUGGGUAUGGGUGCAGAGCUACGCGACCAUCGUGCACAACAGUCGCUCCUCCAGGCCACACUGUAUCGUCAGCGUCAACUAUGUCCUCACAGACACAGAAUACAAAGGGCUGCAGCUCUCCCUGGAUCAGAUCUCAGCCUCCAAACCAGCCUUCUCCUAUACCAGCAGCUCCACCCCCACCAUGACUGACAACAGAAAGGGGGCCAAAUCCCGGCUCUCCAGCUCAAAGUCAAAAUCCAGGACUUCCCCAUACCCUCAGUAUUCGGGAUUUCACACAGAAAGAUCGGAAUCUGAUCAUGACAGCCAGUGGGGCGGAAGUCCCUUGACCGACACGGCCUCUCCGCAGCUUCUGGACCCCGCCGAUAGGCCUGGCUCCCAGCACGACGCAUCGUGCGCCUACAGACAGUUUUCGGACCGCAGCUCUCUCUGCUAUGGCUUUGCGCUUGACCACUCGAGGCUGGUGGAAGAGAGGCAUUUCCAUACCCAGGCCUGUGAAGGAGGCCGAUGUGAGGCAGGCAGGUACUUCCUGGGAACGCCGCAGGCCGGGAGGGAGCCCUGGUGGGGCUCUCGCGCAGCCUUGCCCCUGACAAAGGCCUCCCCAGAAAGCAGAGAAGCCUAUGAAAACAGCAUGCCUCACAUCGCUUCAGUCCACAGGAUCCAUGGGCGAGGUCAUUGGGAUGAAGAUAGUGUGGUCAGUUCUCCAGACCCUGGGUCGGCCAGUGAAUCAGGUGACCGAUAUCGUACUGAGCAGUAUCAAAGUAGCCCACAUGAACCCAGCAAAAUUGAAACUCUUAUAAGAGCCACUCAGCAAAUGAUUAAAGAAGAAGAGAACAGAUUACAGCUAAGGAAAGCCCCCUCAGACCAACUGGCUUCCAUUAAUGGGGCUGGGAAAAAACACUCCCUGUGUUUUGCAAACUACCAACAGCCCCCACCAACAGGUGAAGUCUGCCAUGGCUCUGCUCUUGCCAACACUUCACCAUGUGACCAUAUCCAGCAGAGAGAGGGAAAAAUGUUGAGCCCCCAUGAAAAUGACUAUGACAACAGUCCCACCGCACUAUCUCGGAUAAGUAGUCCCAAUUCGGAUCGCAUUUCAAAAUCCAGUUUGAUCCUAGCUAAAGACUAUCUGCAUUCGGAUAUAUCUCCUCAUCAGACAGCAGGAGACCACCCUACUGUCUCUCCAAACUGCUUUGGCUCUCACCGGCAGUAUUUUGACAAGCAUGCUUACACAUUAACUGGAUAUGCCCUGGAGCACUUAUAUGACAGCGAAACCAUUAGAAACUAUUCCUUGGGCUGUAAUGGCUCACACUUUGAUGUAACUUCCCAUCUGAGGAUGCAACCAGACCCAGCACAAGGACACAAGGGAACAUCUGUUAUAAUAACCAACGGAAGCUGAUGUUUUGCUGAAAUAUUUUGUUCUUUAAGGAUCUCUGAAACAUAUUUAUAGUUUAAUACCCCAUUACCAGCAUUUACUAUGCCACAGAUUGUUAGAGAGUAUAACUUAAGUUACUGGGUAUUUGAUACGUGUUCCUAUAAAAUCAAAGAAAACAUAGCACUAGCAUUCAGGGUUAUACACAGAAAAGGGAGCUAAAUUGAAUACACAAAUUUCCCCUCUAAUUAUAUGGGAACCAGAAUAGAUAAAUUUUGACUUGAAAAAUAUUCAUGUAGAUCAAGUGUGCAUAUAUACUACAUGAGAGGACUGAUGAAUGACAACAUUGCAUUGUGACUAUCCAGUGAUCCUCAAACACACAAACUAUUACUUACAAACUGCGGUAUACAUUUUACAUAUGGAAAUAUAGGCUAUGUAAUGUAAAUACAUCAAAAAUGGGUAAUUUUCUUUGACUCUGUCACACUAAACUUCUUAACGAAAUUUCCAUUCCCAAAAUAACUGAGAAAGAGAGAGAUACAUCUUAUAAACUGACUUCUUUGUGGUUUCAAAUCAGCCAGCUCAUUUGGUUCAGGCAUAAAUUAGAGAAAUGGUUCUGGAUAUGGUGCAAAAAUGAGUUUUCACCUGGUAUCCAUUAUAAACAAUCAGGAAGAGGUAAUUUUUCACCUUGCUUUUCAGUUAGACAAGGACCAGGAUUGCACUGACAUGGCGCUGAGGGUUUUUCUAAGUAAGAACACUGAGAUAUUGGGACACACAUCAAAAACCUGGAGUGCUCAAUUGGAAGUAGUUCUAUGAAUAUGGAAAGGCCAGAGGCAGAGUGAAAUAAAAUGCUAUCUCAAAGUUUAACACAAUUUAAGGGCUCAGCAUAAGUAAACAACAUAUUUGGGGUUUGCUUGUAAAACCAACUAAAUAAAAAAUUCAAACCAAUUCACCCAGAAAAAAGACCAAUAGGUGCAAAAAUAAAAGGAAAACCAGUGAAGUGCCACAUGACAGCAGUGUUAAGUGUUUGAAAACGUUUCAAAGCACAUAUGUGCCAAUGUGACAACAUGUGGAAAGCCUCAGGAGAGAGUCUAAGAUAAAAGCUUAGGCUGAUAGACAAGUAGUUAAGAGCUAAGAGCAGUACUCUGAAGGAAUAGGCAAAAUGUUUAUUUUCCUUAUUGUUUGUAAACAACAAACUUGGUCUUACAUCUGUGUGGUAUAGUAGAAAGGCCAGCUGACUAGAUCUCUGGAUUCUAAUUUUGGCCCUACCUGUAACUUAAUUUUGUGACCACAGUUGUACCAUUCACCGUGCCUGGGCUCUAGUUUCCUGGUUUGUAAGGCAGCCCCAGCGUUCAUGUUCUGUGAUAGAGCAGAACUGAACUUAUUACCUAAUUAACUCUCUGCUAUGAGUUGUCAAGACUGAUCAUUCUGUUUUUUCUGUACACAGAAGUUUAGAUGCUUUGUGACUUAAGCAGGUGUGUGGGCUCCUUUAGGCAGGUUACAGUUAACUUUCUAGAUUUAGCCAAAAUGUAGUUGGUAGAAAUUUAUGACAGAGAAGAAAAAUAGCAAGAUUUAUUUAAUGCUCUAUUCUCUAGUAAUUAAAGCAAAAUGAUAUAAGUGAUUAGAGAGAUUUCAUAGAUAAUAUUUCCUAGGAGUCCCGUGCCCAAAACUCUUGCCAUAUUUAAGGAAGGGAAUGUACUGGCAGAACUUGACUUACAAUUUUGGAAACAGAACAUGAAAUUGAAUACUCAGGGAUUAGUAGUAUAUUUUCAUCAUUUAACACAGUUAUUUCACAGUCCAUAGGUAGGUGACAAUCUGAACGAUAAUAUGAAAGAUGAGUACUGGGUUGUUUGUAUAUGAAAGGAGAGGCUACAUAAAAUUAAAUAAUGUUAACAUUUGUGCUGUAAAUGCAAAAAAGUGCAAGUAAGUGAGAAAGUUAGUGGUUAUAUAUAUUUUCAAAAAAUUCAAAGUGCAGUUGACCCUUGAAUAACAUGGGUUUGAACUGUGCAGAUUCACUUAUGUGUGGUUUUUUUUCCAAUCAAAUGCAGAUAAAAAACCCAGUAUUUGGAGAAAUGUGAAACCUGAGUAUACAGAGGGCGAUGUUUUGUAUAAGUGAGCGCCACAGGGCCAACAGGCAGGACUUGAGUAUGUGAGAAUUUGAUUAUAUGGGGGUAAUCCUGGAACCAACUCCCUGUUUAUACCAAGGGGUGACCAUACAAUAAAAACUAAGUUUUGAAUUAUACAAAAAAGAGUAUUUAGUAAUUUUGAGAAAAUUAUUUAUGAGAAAUCCUGGAAUACAUAAAAUGGAGUUUUGAUCAAUUUGCAACAUGAAGUAAUGUCUUAAGAAUGCUAAAGGUUUUGUAGAAUUCUGUAGAUUGAUAGAUGUUUGGAAGAAAAAAUAUUUGAUGAAUAUGGUGUAUUUUGGAAAGGUAAUUUUCACAGAUGGGUAUUUCUGGUGGCUAUAUAUUCUACCAAAUGUGCCAGGGACAGAAGCUAAAAGAAAUGGAAACUUAAGAACCAGGGAAAAUGAACUGAUAUUAAAGAAAAGGCUGUCACUAAAGGAAUUUCAGUGGAAUUUUUAUAUGGAAGAUAGUUAACUGGUGAGAAGAAGAAAUUAUGAAUUUCACAGAUGAGAGUAAUCAGAAGGAAUAAUGCUCUUUAAAAUGACAUGACCAAUAUUUUUAAGAGAAUACAGAAUUAACUAAAUUAUAUAUUGAUUCAAAAUUUUGGUAGAUUGACCCAGUUUUAAGUACAUAACCAUUUUAAAAUUUACUGAAUGUCAAUAAUUUUAUAGUAGCAGUUUUAUUACAUUACAUAAAAUGUCAUAUUGACUCACUAUAUUGUAUAGCUUACAUUUUUUGCAAUAUGGCAUGAUUAUCACAAAAUGACCCAAGGUAAGUUAAGACAUUUGAUGACAAUGUACUUUCUUAAUAUACAUGUGAAUGUGUUAAAAUGUGUUUAUAAUCUACAUUAUUUUGUUCUGUGCAGCAACAUAUUUCCUCAUAAUGAAGAUGUCAUCUGUGUCUUUUAAAAAUAGUAUAUAAAAUAACUACGUUCCCGAUAAUUUAAUCAGUUAAACUUAAUAUGGCUUUAGUUUUAAUUCUUGAUUUCCAUAACUUUGCCAAAUGUUGAGAAACAUGAAACUUGAUUGAAAUAGAUACAGAAGUAUGAUUUUCAUAUCACCUUGGGGAUACAUAAAAAUGUGCUCUAUCCAAUUACUGGUAUAAUAUGUAUCAAUUCAUUAGAUGAUACAUAGCUCAUGGUUUUGUAGAAUUCUGGUUUCUAGUGAUAAUAAGUAUCUUUAUUGCCCAUUUCACCUGCCAUACCUACUUUAAAAAUUUGGAUGACCAAAGAAGUGAAUGAAGUUUCCCCAAUCUUUCUUGGGAAAAUUCUGUUUAAAUUGUUAUUGGGAAUAUAUAGAUUUGAUGUGUUAUUUUGGGAUGUGUAAUAUUAAUGUCACAAUCACUACAGGUCAGAUAUUUAGGUGUGCUUCGGUCCACAAGUCUUUUGUCAUAUUGUGCUCGCUUACCUAAACUGUAAUUGCCUGAUAAAAGAUAAUAUGACAGUGCUGAGGUGACAUUCAAAAUGAGACGGGAUGCAAUAAAUGAUUGCCUUCAGUAUUUACACAGAAAAACCACUUGCUCUUUCUUGGUUAUAUUUCAUAGGGCUAGAUUGUUUCCAUCGGGCACUAUUCUUAAUUCACUCUAUACCGUGUUGUCACAUGCUGCCUCUGGGCAGAGAAUCCCACUUAAAAUAAGCUUUAGGGGAUCUUCUAGAAAAGGGUAGUGUGCUCCAAUUUUUAUUUCUCCUUCUUAUGGGGGAUGAGGAUCAAUUAUAGUACAAGACCAUUUGGAAAAUAUGCAUAUAUAUUUUAAAAUGAAAUACAAGAUUUCCGCCCUCAAGAUCUAAACCAAGUAAGUUUGAUGGAUGGCAGCACAGAUAAAGAAAUCUUCUGAAUACACAUUUGAUUUUUAUAGCUCUCUCUUUCAAGAGUAGGAUAUUACUAAGAUAUUCAGUGCAAUCUAUCAGUCCUAGUAGUAUUUAGAAGUGACAGAGUGAAUGCUGAUAUUUGGAAAAUUGAGCAUUUGACCAUUUUGGGGUCACUCACCUGGCCUAGUGGAAUAGCUUACACUUUAAUACAAUCAAACACAGUCUUUCUGAUAUAAAAUGUUUGAAUGCCCAGAUUUGGUUCCCUAGUUCACUCAAAUCAUAGAUGUUGACAUACAUCCUGUUUUCAUAAUGAUUUUAAAAAGAAUGUAAAUCCUAUGGUCCUCCAAAUAAAUGAUUCAACGUUUAUGUAAAUGUCAAGUUUUUGUGAAUAGGGAUUUAUGUCUAAGACAGAAAAAUCUACUGAACUAGUUCUUACUGUGGAACUAAUUGUGGAUAAAACAUUCGUUAUCAUCUAAAUUUUAAAUGAAUGACAACAGUUAUGGACACAUGCAAAAGGUAUCAGACAUAGAAAAUAUUGUUGGGGGAAAUUUCUGUGUGGUGCUAAUUUCUUGUAAGGGUUGUACAGAUAGUGCUUAACUCAAAAAGUGAGAGUGUGGUCAUUGCCAAAUAGGGGUUUGCUCAGAGUUCCUUCUCUAGGACUGUAUGCAGAAAGCAUACACACACACAUACGCACACAGAAAAAUAUGAUUUUUAUAUCAUAUUCAUGAAAAUGUGCCAUAUCCAAUUAUAACACACACACACACACACACACACACACACACACACACACAUAAAUAAAUAAAUGAUGGUUCACAUAAGAAAUCCUAAUUGCUAAUUUUAAACCAAACAUUUGUAGUUUUGUUUAUUGCAACUUUGCUGCAUGGGACUUUGCUUUCAUAAAUCUAUAUGGGGUUGGGGUUAAUUUGCCCUAAUUUGCUGACCUGGGACACAUGUAAUCACUGUUAAACUUACACCCGGUAACCCUGAUGUGUUUACAUUUCAAAAGAAAUGAAAUUGGCCUGGAAAAAAAUUUUGGAAGUACUGUAAGUCUUUUUUCUUUUUUUUUCCGAAGGGAAAUAUUUCAAAAAAGGAAACAUUAUGAGUAGACACUUCAAAAAAGAUAAAAUAUUUUACAUUUGUUUUUUGACUAAUGUGCUAUAAAAAGGAUUAUAUUUGUGAGAAAAGAUACUGAUCGCCAAUAUUUCAAAUACCGUCUUGCAAUGUAUAGUUUUUAGUGACAUUGUAGUAUAAAGCUGUAAUUUGAAAUUUUACUUUGGAAUGUAAAGUAGAAAAUAUUAGCUAUGUCAAUGAUAUCUUGCAAAGUGUUCCCAUUUAUAAUUAUUUAUAUUGUAAAUAGCUUUCUGAAGUAAAUUCGAAGUUAAUGUGCAUAAAAUGUAUUUAUUAUGUGAGGAAUUUUUUGGUUUAAAAUAUAGUUACCAAUAUGCACUUUGA